AAGUUAUAAUUCAAGUAAACAUUAAGAAAAAGCAAAGGUAGAAAAAUUACGCACCCAAAAGACAGUGGUUUUGGUUUUUGAAAGUAGGAAUAGUUUCAGGAUAUGGCCAAGGGCACCAUGUCACUCAUGUCACUGUGGAUGGCAUUGAGUUUGCAUUGCUGCCUUUGAUACUGUGUCUUGAGAUGAAAAACAUGUUUCAUCAGACCAUUAAAUUUUUAAAUUACCUGCUUGGAGUUACCUGUCAGUGGAUAAACUAGCAGAGUGGCUUACUGUUCUUAGAGAAAGAUGAAAGGCAAAAUGACUUGUGUCAACAGAAUGAAAAUUAAAUAGCUCUGGCAUUUGGACUGGGAAUUCUUUCUGUGGUAGAAAAUAAAAUGGGAAGUCUUUGAAAAGAAGGAUUUUGAUUUUAAUCUUACCUGGAUGAUCUGUUAUCUGAAAUGUCCAGGGCACCAUAGAGUUUUUAUUGACACUAAGUAUCAGAGUUCACCCUAAAAAGCCAAGGAGGAAAGGAUAAUGUAAAAAUACUUCCUAGCCCCUGUAGACCUUACAAAAAAGAUCAUUCUGGAGUCCCUGAUUCCUUCUCUUGAAUGGCAUAUAGCAGACUCUAUAUGGACAAUUUAAAUAAUGCUACAUACAAUGUAAGUUAAUACACGUGUUUCUGCUGCUUUUUACUGUAUAUAAUUUGUACUACUUUUGUUUUCUCUUUCACACUGAGCCCUAUUCUUGAGGUUGAAAAAAGGAAAGUUAAGUAAUAUUAAAUAACUUAAAUAAUCAAAUAAACUAAAAGUGAAGGCAGAACUUUUAGUAGGUAUGAUCCUAUCUAGGGAUACAUUUUUUCAGUGGCAAAAAAAUAGACCUUACUGUUCUUACAAAAAAUGAAAAAAAAAUGAAAUCAAAUUGAUCAAAUGUUUCAUCUUGUGCUGGCUCAAAGUGAGUUAAGUGCAGUUAAGAGGAUUGAGGAAUGUAGAAUGAGCACAAGGACAGUUUUGGGCUACUUGCUGGUUUAUGCCUUUUCUAGAAUCUCAUGAAGUCCUUUAGCGGCAUGAAUGACAUGAGCAGCUUUGGAAUUUAUAUUCAUUCUUCAUUCAUCCAUUUACUCAUGUAGCAUUGAGCACCUGCCUGGUAGCAGGUACUGUGCCAGAUGGUGUAUGUACAAGGAUGAGCAAAACCAGGUCAACCCCUGUUCUUUGGAAGGUAACUGCAUGGUAGAGAGAGAUAUAUUAAUCAAAUAAUCCCAUUGAUUAAUGAUAAUUACAGGCAAAACUCAAUUAUAUGAGGGAAUGUAACAAGGAGCUUGACUAGACUGGGUGGGUGUGGAGGUGUAGCUGAGGAGCAGGGUUCAUUGAAGUCUUUCCUGUGCAAGUGGCACUUGAGCGGAGAUUUCAAGGACAAGGUAGCAAUCAAUGGGGAGAACGGUAUGAAGGUAGGGAAGAACGUUCCAUACCAUGGAAGGAACAAGUGCAAAGAGCCUGUGGCAGGAAGGAAUGAGGUAAGGUUAGGGAACUAGAAGAAAGCAGACAGAUGUGCCUGAGCACAAAGAGGGAAGAGGCUGAGCUUGGUCCAAGAUGACCAACUGGUCCAAGUUGGUCCAAGGUGAGGCUGGAAAGGAAAGUAGAGGCCAGACCAUUCAGACCAUAUAGUCUAUGUUCCAGAUUUUGGAUAUUCUUCCAAGAACGUUGGUACCAUUCGUGGAAGGGUUUGUUUGUAUUGAUAAAAAUCAUUCAACUAGGCCAAACCAAUUUGGGCAGUUCUGGUUGUGGUAUUAUGCUCAGGAGAAUUAAAGUAGCAUCGGUGUCAAUUCUGUGGAAGGUGAGAUCCAGCCUUAGGUAGGAUUGUUUUAAGUUUCCAGAUUAAGCUGACGAAUAAUUUGUAUUCUGGAACAAUAUUCAUCGUAGAUUCUAAAUGAAUACAACCAAUGUUCACUCUCAUUAUAAAGAAAGCCAUGAGAUGUGGCAUGCUGUUUGGCAUGUGGCAAACCUGAGGCACGAGUGGCUAAAUGGUAACAAUAAAUCUGCUAGCAAUGAUCCUAUUUAAAAUAUCUCCACAAUGCAUGUAUCCAGAAACUGCCAUGUAAAAGCUCUAAAGAAAAAGAGCCAAACUCAAGUAAACUAAGUACUUGCUUGUCCUCUGUUGUAUUUUCAAUCCUCCCAAUUUACAUAGGCUUUCUCAUGCCAUGAAGAUGUAGGCAUUCUUACCUUUAGUCAGUGUUUGAAGAAUUUCCAACCAGGAAAGGUUAAGUGAUUUGUUACACAGUAGUUGGUGGCAGAACCAAAGUUAGAACUCUAAUGUGACUCCAACAUCUACAUUCUUUCUAAACUGUGUUGAAGUAGUGGAGGUGUAACAUAAAUCUAAAGGAACGUAAAUCUCAAUGAUUCUGAUCACCUUUGUUAUUUGGUUGUGAAUUAAGAAGGAUGGGAAUCUUGCUGAUUUCUAGUCUUUGAUGGAUCUCAAUGUAGAAUUUAACAAAGUCUUGUUUUUUUUUAAUGAACUUGGAGCAAUAGGACACUUUUAAUUAUAAAAAUAUCUACGAAAAAUGUGAAUGUCUAACUACAUUUUGAAGACCCUCUUUGUAGACCUUAUAGGCAACAGGGACCAUAUGAGUGAUGGGACAAAUUCUGGUUUUAGAAAGACUACUUUAAAAGCAGUGUGGAUAAUACACCAGAUUGGGAAGGGCUGAUGGCAGAGGGUGUCUAAUAAACGUGCAUGUAUUAUGAUGUGUUCUGUGAGGAAGCUGGGAGGAUAGCCCUCAAGGCCACUUUGAGCCUUCCUUUGUCACUGAGGCAUUCCAUUAGUGACUCCUGAAUUCCACUUGGGAAAAGAGCCCCUCAGUGUCUCCAGCGUCUGAGAGAAGUCUGUGAAGAUGACUGACCUUGGAGCCCCUCUUAGCCUCUCCACGACUGAGUAAAUGUCAUCUCCUGACAGCACCCCCUUCCAGAGUGUUCUUGUUAGAUUUAACAAAAAUCCCAGUUGUCAAUUUUUUCUUUUGAUAGAUGAAUUCAGGCCAUUCCCAGUCAGCAUAAGCCUCUACUUGAUUUUAUUUCUAUGUUUAUUUACUACUUAUUUUUCUUUGUUGUAUCCUCUUUUUCUCUUUUAUUUUUGUUGGUGUGAUGAAAUUUCUUUUGACUCUCCUCUUUGCCUCCGGUUAAUUUGGAAGGUCGACUACAGUUCUUAAUUUACUAAGUAAUUGACAUGUUCAAAGAAUCUUAAUUGAAUGUCUACUUGUUUAUCAUUGUAUGAAAAUAAUGAAAAUGCCUUUGUCUGAUGUGCCUAGUCCCCAUCCCCUGCACUGAUAUGAGAACUUAAGAAUGUUCUUCCUUUCCCACUCUCACACUUCCCCCAGACAGUGCACCCUGCUCCAUACGUGGGUUUUGUGGAAAUAAUUUAAAACUUACAGUUGCAGAUCAUUGCUAGGUUUCCUCUUACAGUAUUUCUCUUCUGUUUCAAGAAUCCUUUCUUAACACUUACAUCACAUACGUUCAAUGACAACAUCAUUCUGGACAUCUGCUCCUGUCUUGUGAUCUCUGUUCUAAUCUAAUGAUCAGAAGACUUCUCUUAUUUUCGUUAAAUACCCCCAACUCUCUGAAUUCCAGUACAGGAGAAAUCAAUGGUUCUGCCAAUUAUGAGAUGUUUAUAUUUCACAACGGAGGUGUACAAAUUUUAUGCAAAUAUCCUGACAUUGUCCAGCAAUUUAAAAUGCAGUUGCUGAAAGGGGGGCAAAUACUCUGCGAUCUCACUAAGACAAAAGGAAGUGGAAACACAGUGUCCAUUAAGAGUCUGAAAUUCUGCCAUUCUCAGUUAUCCAACAACAGUGUCUCUUUUUUUCUAUACAACUUGGACCAUUCUCAUGCCAACUAUUACUUCUGCAACCUAUCAAUUUUUGAUCCUCCUCCUUUUAAAGUAACUCUUACAGGAGGAUAUUUGCAUAUUUAUGAAUCACAACUUUGUUGCCAGCUGAAGUUCUGGUUACCCAUAGGAUGUGCAGCCUUUGUUGUAGUCUGCAUUUUGGGAUGCAUACUUAUUUGUUGGCUUACAAAAAAGAAGUAUUCAUCCAGUGUGCACGACCCUAACGGUGAAUACAUGUUCAUGAGAGCAGUGAACACAGCCAAAAAAUCUAGACUCACAGAUGUGACCCUAUAAUAUGGAACUCUGGCACCCAGGCAUGAAGCACGUUGGCCAGUUUUCCUCAACUUGAAGUGCAAGAUUCUCUUAUUUCCGGGACCACGGAGAGUCUGACUUAACUACAUACAUCUUCUGCUGGUGUUUUGUUCAAUCUGGAAGAAUGACUGUAUCAGUCAAUGGGGAUUUUAACAGACUGCCUUGGUACUGCCGAGUCCUCUCAAAACAAACACCCUCUUGCAACCAGCUUUGGAGAAAGCCCAGCUCCUGUGUGCUCACUGGGAGUGGAAUCCCUGUCUCCACAUCUGCUCCUAGCAGUGCAUCAGCCAGUAAAACAAACACAUUUACAAGAAAAAUGUUUUAAAGAUGCCAGGGGUACUGAAUCUGCAAAGCAAAUGAGCAGCCAAGGACCAGCAUCUGUCCGCAUUUCACUAUCAUACUACCUCUUCUUUCUGUAGGGAUGAGAAUUCCUCUUUUAAUCAGUCAAGGGAGAUGCUUCAAAGCUGGAGCUAUUUUAUUUCUGAGAUGUUGAUGUGAACUGUACAUUAGUACAUACUCAGUACUCUCCUUCAAUUGCUGAACCCCAGUUGACCAUUUUACCAAGACUUUAGAUGCUUUCUUGUGCCCUCAAUUUUCUUUUUAAAAAUACUUCUACAUGACUGCUUGACAGCCCAACAGCCACUCUCAAUAGAGAGCUAUGUCUUACAUUCUUUCCUCUGCUGCUCAAUAGUUUUAUAUAUCUAUGCAUACAUAUAUACACACAUAUGUAUAUAAAAUUCAUAAUGAAUAUAUUUGCCUAUAUUCUCCCUACAAGAAUAUUUUUGCUCCAGAAAGACAUGUUCUUUUCUCAAAUUCAGUUAAAAUGGUUUACUUUGUUCAAGUUAGUGGUAGGAAACAUUGCCCGGAAUUGAAAGCAAAUUUAUUUUAUUAUCCUAUUUUCUACCAUUAUCUAUGUUUUCAUGGUGCUAUUAAUUACAAGUUUAGUUCUUUUUGUAGAUCAUAUUAAAAUUGCAAACAAAAUCAUCUUUAAUGGGCCAGCAUUCUCAUGGGGUAGAGCAGAAUAUUCAUUUAGCCUGAAAGCUGCAGUUACUAUAGGUUGCUGUCAGACUAUACCCAUGGUGCCUCUGGGCUUGACAGGUCAAAAUGGUCCCCAUCAGCCUGGAGCAGCCCUCCAGACCUGGGUGGAAUUCCAGGGUUGAGAGACUCCCCUGAGCCAGAGGCCACUAGGUAUUCUUGCUCCCAGAGGCUGAAGUCACCCUGGGAAUCACAGUGGUCUACCUGCAUUCAUAAUUCCAGGAUCUGUGAAGAGCACAUAUGUGUCAGGGCACAAUUCCCUCUCAUAAAAACCACACAGCCUGGAAAUUGGCCCUGGCCCUUCAAGAUAGCCUUCUUUAGAAUAUGAUUUGGCUAGAAAGAUUCUUAAAUAUGUGGAAUAUGAUUAUUCUUAGCUGGAAUAUUUUCUCUACUUCCUGUCUGCAUGCCCAAGGCUUCUGAAGCAGCCAAUGUCGAUGCAACAACAUUUGUAACUUUAGGUAAACUGGGAUUAUGUUGUAGUUUAACAUUUUGUAACUGUGUGCUUAUAGUUUACAAGUGAGACCCGAUAUGUCAUUAUGCAUACUUAUAUUAUCUUAAGCAUGUGUAAUGCUGGAUGUGUACAGUACAGUACUGAACUUGUAAUUUGAAUCUAGUAUGGUGUUCUGUUUUCAGCUGACUUGGACAACCUGACUGGCUUUGCACAGGUGUUCCCUGAGUUGUUUGCAGGUUUCUGUGUGUGGGGUGGGGUAUGGGGAGGAGAACCUUCAUGGUGGCCCACCUGGCCUGGUUGUCCAAGCUGUGCCUCGACACAUCCUCAUCCCCAGCAUGGGACACCUCAAGAUGAAUAAUAAUUCACAAAAUUUCUGUGAAAUCAAAUCCAGUUUUAAGAGGAGCCACUUAUCAAAGAGAUUUUAACAGUAGUAAGAAGGCAAAGAAUAAACAUUUGAUAUUCAGCAACUGAAAA